GAGAGAGGGCGCGGCCAACUCCAGGGGGGACGGCAGGCCGAGAGCGCGGCGCCCGGGCCUGGCGCGGAGCCUGAGCCCGCCGGACGGGAGGCGGCCCCGCCGCGGGCUCGGCCCCGGCCCCAGCCCCGCCAGCAUGGCCGGCCGGACUGUACGGGCCGAGACCCGGAGCCGGGCCAAGGAUGACAUCAAGAAGGUGAUGGCGACCAUCGAGAAGGUCCGGAGAUGGGAGAAGCGAUGGGUGACUGUGGGCGACACUUCCCUUCGUAUCUUCAAGUGGGUGCCAGUGGUGGAUCCCCAGGAGGAGGAGCGAAGGCGGGCAGGUGGCGGGGCAGAGAGAUCCCGUGGCCGGGAACGUCGGGGCAGGGGCGCCAGUCCCCGAGGGGGUGGCCCUCUCAUCCUGCUGGAUCUUAAUGAUGAGAACAGCAACCAGAGUUUCCAUUCGGAAGGUUCCCUGCAAAAGGGCACAGAGCCCAGUCCUGGGGGCACCCCCCAGCCCAGCCGCCCUGUGUCACCUGCCGGACCCCCAGAAGGGGUCCCUGAGGAGGCUCAGCCCCCACGGCUGGGCCAAGAGAGAGAUCCCGGGGGCAUAACUGCUGGCAGCACCGACGAACCCCCAAUGCUGACCAAGGAGGAGCCUGUUCCAGAACUGCUGGAAGCUGAGGAUUCGGGAGUGAGAAUGACGAGGAGAGCCCUUCACGAGAAGGGGCUGAAGACAGAGCCCCUCAGGAGGCUCCUGCCCAGGAGGGGCCUCCGGACAAAUGUCCGGCCCAGUUCCAUGGCGGUGCCGGACACCAGAGCUCCCGGGGGAGGCAGCAAGGCCCCGAGGGCACCCAGAACAAUCCCCCAGGGUAAGGGGAGGUGAGUGGGCUCCCCAAGCAAGCCAAGACCCCUAAAGCCUCCCUUGGCUGCCCCAAGAUCCAGCCACUACCUGUGCCCCGAGGGCGGAAAGAGCUUCCCAGCUCACCCACCGCGGUAACAUCGGAGGGCGAGCGGCCCCACACCUGCCCGAACCUAAGGCCACAGCACCCAUCUGGCUCGCCACUGGCGCCCGAAUGCAUGGGAAGGGCUUAGGGCAGAACUCGGACCACAUCCAGUGCCUGAGGCCGCCUUGCUAGAGGCCUAGGGGAGGGGUGCACUGGGCUGCCUCGCCCACCUCCUCACGCACCCAUGCGGCCACCCUCCCAGCGGUCUGAGUGUGCCAUGCGAGGCGCCUGCCACCCCGGGAGAGGCGCCGAGUCCCGAGUCCUGCCGGCACUGAGCCUCCGGGUCCACAGCGGGCAAGGGCCGUGGCGGGGACAAGCGCAGGGGACCCGCCGGCCUCCCGCCUUCUGCAGCACCACGAGAUGCCCACGUGGCACCUGGACGUCCAUGCAUAUGUUGAGGCCCGUGCACGCGCAGAGACCCCAGCGCAGAAGCCGCCCCGCACGCCAGGGCUUAUGUAUGCCAGCGCUGGGAGACCUCCAGCGCCCGAGGACAUACGGCAAGUGGUUCCACCAGGGUGUCAGCCUAGCAGGCCAACCUGGGAACCCAUGUGGACAAGCGGCCUUUCAGCCCAGGCGCCCGCCUCGGGUGGAGGCGUGGAGACUUCUGGCGCAGCCCUGAGCUGGUGGCCUAACCUACCUGGAAAAUCCUAGCCCGAGAAGCAGCGCGAGUGAGCCUUUUGGGUGGUUCCAAGGCCCUUCACCAAGCUCUCACUUCCUGACUUCACCGUUGGGUCUGUUGUACUAGGAAAUAAUAACGCCUCCCAUUUAUCAAGGGUUUACUCUGUACCAGGCAUUGUGACUGAUGUAAUUUAGUUCUCACUGCAUCCCUGUGGCAUGGAUAUUCUCAUUAUCUGCAUUUUGCAGAUGGAGAAAUUGAGUCUCUGAGAGGUUAAGGAACCUGCCCAAAGUCAGCAAUGCAGUACCACUUCUUGUGCUGGGACACAGCGGGGUUAAGGCCGUGGGUUAACAGGGCCUCCAUUUAUGGAGAGCAUUCAUUUUUCUCUGGUGAAUUACAGAAAACGCUUUCUACACUGAAGUGAGUAGAUACUCCCUGGGAUGAAAGUCAACAUUCGUACCAAUGAUUGAGAUGACAGAAAUUUCACGCUUCAAGCCAAUGCUUUAGGUUCAGCCCAUGGAAUUCUGGAAUGACCUUUUCUCAGUCGUCACCAGGGUGAUGUUGGUGAAGGAAGCUCCAUUCCAG